ACACAAAGCCCAGACGCGGAGAAAAUGGCGGCAGGGGUCGAAGCGGCGGCGGAGGUGGCGGCGACGGAGAUCAAAAUGGAGGAAGAGAGCGGCGCGCCCGGCGUGCCGAGCGGCAACGGGGCUCCGGGCCCUAAGGGUGAAGGAGAACGACCUGCUCAGAAUGAGAAGAGGAAGGAGAAAAACAUAAAAAGAGGAGGCAAUCGCUUUGAGCCAUAUGCCAAUCCAACUAAAAGAUACAGAGCCUUCAUUACAAACAUACCUUUUGAUGUGAAAUGGCAGUCACUUAAAGACCUGGUUAAAGAAAAAGUUGGUGAGGUAACAUACGUGGAGCUCUUAAUGGACGCUGAAGGAAAGUCAAGGGGAUGUGCUGUUGUUGAAUUCAAGAUGGAAGAGAGCAUGAAAAAAGCUGCGGAAGUCCUAAACAAGCAUAGUCUGAGCGGAAGACCACUGAAAGUCAAAGAAGAUCCUGAUGGUGAACAUGCCAGGAGAGCAAUGCAAAAGGUGAUGGCUACGACUGGUGGGAUGGGUAUGGGACCAGGUGGCCCAGGAAUGAUUACUAUCCCACCCAGUAUCCUAAAUAAUCCCAACAUCCCAAAUGAGAUUAUCCAUGCAUUACAGGCUGGAAGACUUGGAAGCACAGUAUUUGUAGCAAAUCUGGAUUAUAAAGUUGGCUGGAAGAAACUGAAGGAAGUAUUUAGUAUGGCUGGUGUGGUGGUCCGAGCAGACAUUCUUGAAGAUAAAGAUGGAAAAAGUCGUGGAAUAGGCACUGUUACUUUUGAACAGUCCAUUGAAGCUGUGCAAGCUAUAUCUAUGUUCAAUGGCCAGCUGCUAUUUGAUAGACCAAUGCACGUCAAGAUGGAUGAGAGGGCCUUACCAAAAGGAGAUUUCUUCCCUCCUGAGCGUCCACAACAACUUCCCCAUGGCCUUGGUGGUAUUGGCAUGGGGUUAGGACCAGGAGGGCAACCCAUUGAUGCCAAUCACCUGAAUAAAGGCAUCGGAAUGGGAAACAUAGGUCCCGCAGGAAUGGGAAUGGAAGGCAUAGGAUUUGGAAUAAAUAAAAUGGGAGGAAUGGAGGGGCCCUUUGGUGGUGGUAUGGAAAACAUGGGUCGAUUUGGAUCUGGGAUGAACAUGGGCAGGAUAAAUGAAAUCCUAAGUAAUGCACUGAAGAGAGGAGAGAUCAUUGCAAAGCAGGGAGGAGGUGGAGGUGGAGGAAGCGUCCCUGGGAUCGAGAGGAUGGGUCCUGGCAUUGACCGCCUCGGGGGUGCCGGCAUGGAGCGCAUGGGCGCGGGCCUGGGCCACGGCAUGGAUCGCGUGGGCUCCGAGAUCGAGCGCAUGGGCCUGGUCAUGGACCGCAUGGGCUCCGUGGAGCGCAUGGGCUCCGGCAUUGAGCGCAUGGGCCCGCUGGGCCUCGACCACAUGGCCUCCAGCAUUGAGCGCAUGGGCCAGACCAUGGAGCGCAUUGGCUCUGGCGUGGAGCGCAUGGGUGCCGGCAUGGGCUUCGGCCUUGAGCGCAUGGCCGCUCCCAUCGACCGUGUGGGCCAGACCAUUGAGCGCAUGGGCUCUGGCGUGGAGCGCAUGGGCCCUGCCAUCGAGCGCAUGGGCCUGAGCAUGGAGCGCAUGGUGCCCGCAGGUAUGGGAGCUGGCCUGGAGCGCAUGGGCCCCGUGAUGGAUCGCAUGGCCACCGGCCUGGAGCGCAUGGGCGCCAACAAUCUGGAGCGGAUGGGCCUGGAGCGCAUGGGCGCCAACAGCCUCGAGCGCAUGGGCCUGGAGCGCAUGGGUGCCAACAGCCUCGAGCGCAUGGGCCCUGCCAUGGGCCCGGCCCUGGGCGCUGGCAUUGAGCGCAUGGGCCUGGCCAUGGGUGGCGGUGGCGGUGCCAGCUUUGACCGUGCCAUCGAGAUGGAGCGUGGCAACUUCGGAGGAAGCUUCGCAGGUUCCUUUGGUGGAGCUGGAGGCCAUGCUCCUGGGGUGGCCAGGAAGGCCUGCCAGAUAUUUGUGAGAAAUCUGCCAUUCGAUUUCACAUGGAAGAUGCUAAAGGACAAAUUCAACGAGUGCGGCCACGUGCUGUACGCCGACAUCAAGAUGGAGAAUGGGAAGUCCAAGGGGUGUGGCGUGGUUAAGUUCGAGUCGCCAGAGGUGGCCGAGAGAGCCUGCCGGAUGAUGAAUGGCAUGAAGCUGAGUGGCCGAGAGAUUGACGUUCGAAUUGAUAGAAACGCUUAAGCAGUUGCCUUUUUUAAACAUCGAUACGAGACCUCUGAAUUUGUAUUUUUUCUUGUUAACCAUUUUAAUUUGUUGGCUGGAUGUAUAAAGAUGUUUAAAAAAUUCAGUUGCUUUUUGGGGUAAUUUGAAUUACUUUUUUAAUGACUGGGGUUCCAUUUGACUGUUUGCAUUGAGAUUGCAAUGUGCGCAAUUUUUUUUGUAGUUGUGGCAUCUUGUUGACAUCGAAUAUGACUUUGAUAAUAAAUACCGGUUCCUGAAAA